ACUCUGCUCAGCUCCGCUCCAGGAAGGCCACCUCCUCCUCCCCCUCCUCCUCCCGCUGUCACCACUCACCGCUCAUAACCUCAAGGGGGUGGGGACCCCAGGGCUGGACACACCCCACCGUGGCCCCAGAGCUCAGCCGGUCGCACGGACGGACAGUUGGAAGCCGGACCCCAGAGCCUGAGGUGGGCAGUGUGCCAGGGUCCCUUGCGGCCUCCUCAAGGUCAUGGGGGCCUUGGCAGGAGCGGUUUUGGCAGAGGGUGGGGCCGGUGCCUCUGGAAGGUAUGAAGAUGUAAAUGAAGCCCUGUCCAGGCUAUGGGCAUCAAGACAGCAUUGCCGGCGGCUGAGCUGGGCCUCUACUCUCUGGUGCUGAGUGGGGCCCUGGCCUAUGCUGGCCGGGGCCUCCUUGAGGCUUCACAAGAUGGGGCCCACAGGAAGGCCUUCCGGGAGUCUGUGCGACCUGGCUGGGAGUACAUUGGCCGGAAGAUGGAUGUGGCUGACUUCGAGUGGGUGAUGUGGUUCACCUCCUUUCGCAACGUCAUCAUCUUUGCCCUCUCCGGACAUGUGCUGUUUGCUAAACUCUGCACGAUGGUUGCCCCAAAGCUCCGCUCCUGGAUGUAUGCUGUGUACGGGGCCUUGGCUGUGAUGGGCACAAUGGGCCCUUGGUACCUGCUGCUGCUGCUUGGUCACUGUGUGGGCCUCUAUGUGGCCUCGCUUUUGGGCCAGCCCUGGCUCUGUCUUGGCCUUGGCUUGGCCAGCCUGGCCUCCUUCAAGAUGGACCCCCUAAUCUCUUGGCAGAGCGGGUUUGUAACAGGCACUUUUGAUCUUCAAGAGGUGCUGUUUCAUGGGGGCAGCAGCUUCACAGUGCUGCGUUGCACCAGCUUUGCACUGGAGAGCUGUGCCCACCCUGACCGCCACUACUCCUUAGCUGACCUGCUCAAGUACAACUUCUACCUGCCCUUCUUCUUCUUCGGGCCCAUCAUGACCUUUGAUCGCUUCCAUGCUCAGGUGAGCCAGGUGGAGCCAGUGAGACGCGAGGGUGAGCUGUGGCACAUCCGAGCCCAGGCAGGCCUAAGCGUGGUGGCCAUCAUGGCCGUCGACAUCUUCUUUCACUUCUUCUACAUCCUCACUAUCCCCAGCGACCUCAAGUUCGCCAACCGCCUCCCAGACAGUGCCCUCGCUGGCCUAGCCUAUUCAAACCUGGUGUAUGACUGGGUGAAGGCGGCCGUCCUCUUUGGUGUUGUCAACACUGUGGCAUGCCUCGACCACCUGGACCCACCCCAGCCUCCCAAGUGCAUCACCGCACUCUACGUCUUUGCGGAAACGCACUUUGACCGUGGCAUCAACGACUGGCUUUGCAAAUAUGUGUAUAACCACAUUGGUGGGGAGCAUUCCGCUGUGAUCCCAGAGCUGGCAGCCACAGUGGCCACAUUUGCCAUCACCACACUGUGGCUUGGGCCUUGUGACAUUGUCUACCUGUGGUCAUUCCUUAACUGCUUUGGCCUCAACUUUGAGCUCUGGAUGCAAAAACUGGCAGAGUGGGGGCCCCUAGCACGAAUUGAGGCCUCUCUGUCAGUGCAGAUGUCCCGUAGGGUCCGGGCCCUGUUUGGAGCCAUGAACUUCUGGGCCAUCAUCAUGUACAACCUUGUGAGCCUGAACAGCCUCAAAUUCACAGAGCUGGUUGCCCGGCGCCUGCUACUCACAGGGUUCCCCCAGACCACGCUGUCCAUCCUGUUUGUCACCUACUGUGGCGUCCAGCUGGUAAAGGAGCGUGAGCGAACCUUGGCACUGGAGGAGGAGCAGAAGCAGGACAAAGAGAAGCCGGAGUAGGAGGGAGCGGGUAGAGGGAUGGGCUCUGCUCAGCUAUUCUUGGGCCAGAUGGGGCCUGACCGAUAGAAUAAAAGACUUUUCUACAACA